GAGAAACUGCUCUGCCUUCCUGAGGGGCAGCCACAGCUCCUGCUGGCCCGUCUCAGCGCCUCUGCGACAACCUCAGGUGCGGGCAAGACAGACGGAGGGAGAGAAGGGAGGAAGGAAAAACGGAUGCAGGAGGAUCCUAGACACGGAGGAGACAGAACCCACAAGAGGGGGCGGCGGUGGCGUGGACGGCGCCGCGAGGGCAUCCCAGCACACAGGACGGGUGGAGGGCUAGUGACAGCGGAACUCUGCCCUUCGACCCGGCCGGGUCACCGCUGAGGACAGACCCUAGAGCGGCACUUCGGGGGUCAGUGAGGUCAACACAACCGCCACAAAGACACCACGAUCACUGUCGCUGCCACUUUCCCUCUUGCGGUCUCAGGAGGGCACAGGGAGGCCUUUGGAGGCUGCGUCACCAGGGACGGCUCCGCCAUGUUGACAGCUAAAAGAGGGGGCGCGCUUGUCUUCUUGUGCUCUGAAUUUCUCAGCUUUCAAUUUAUUUGGUUUUUUUUUUUUUUGAGACAAAGUCUCGCUCUGUCUCCCAGGCUGGAAUGCAGUGGUACAAUCUUGGUUCACUGCAGCCUCAACCUUUCAGGCUCAAGUGAUCUUCCCACCUUGGCCUCCCGAGUAGCUAGGACUACAGGCAUGCGCCACCAUGCCCGGCUAAUUUUCAUUUUUUGUAGAGACGGGGUCUUGCUACAUGGCCCAGGCUGGUCUCAAACUCCCAACCUCAAGCGAUCCUCGCCUCAGCCUCCCAAAGUGCUGGGAUUACAGGUGUGAGCUACCAUGCCUGGCCUCAACUUCUAACACACUAACAGCCGGCAGACAUAAUCCACACAGACACAGGCUCCUGGGGCUAUUGGAUCAUUCUGGAUGAUGUAAAGGGUCCUGAAAUCCGUUUGAGAACCCCUGACCUGGAAAGACUCCAACACAGCGCACGUAAGGAUCUGUUCCAGCACAUUCCACAGCAGCAUUCUUCCUAGCCAGAAAACCCAGACACACCAACUGAGGCUGGAUUAAAGUAUGCAAUCUAAUUGACCAACUAUGUCCACGGGGACAAUUCUGGCCUGCACCUCUUUUGUUUUGGUUUUGUUUUUUGUUUUGCUUUUUUUUUGAGACGGAGUCUUGCUCUGUCGCCCAGGCUGGAGUGCAGUGGUGGGAUCUCAGCUCACUGCAACCUCCCACCUCCCAGGUUCAAGCGAUUCUCCUGCCUCAGCCUCCUAAGUGGAACUACAGACAUGCGCCACCACGUCUGGCUAAUUUUUGUAUUUUUAGUAGAGACGGGGUUUCACCAUGUUGGCACGCUGUUCUAGAACUCCUGACCUCAGGUGAUCCGCCUGCCUUGGCCUCCCAAAGCACCGGGAUUACAAUCAUGAGCCACUGGGCCCCGCCAUACCUGUUUUUAUAAAUCAAGUUUUAUUGGAACAAAGCCACGCCCACCGGUUUACAGAUUGUCUACAGCUGCUUCGGGGCCACAACAGCAGUGAUAAUUGGUUAAGUGCAGGCAGCCACACCUUUGACUUCCAUUUCAACUUACCUCCCAGGCUUCCUUCUACCUUCACCAGCAAAUUUGGCCAUGUCUUCUAUUUCGUACAAGCUUCCUGCAUGGGCAGGGAACACAUUUUAGCCAAGAAGAGGAUGUACUUAUUGGUUCAAGGAACUUCCACCUUCCACAAAGAAACCCCAUUCCAGAACCCCUUGUUCGUGGAGGCUGAGGAGAAAGUCUCCUACAACUGCUGCCGCCAGGGCACUGUCUGUUUGCAAAUCCAGAUGGAAAGGAACACCUUCACGCCAGGAGAGAAGGUCGUCUUCACAACAGAGAUCAACAACCAGACCAGCAAAUGCAUCAAGACGGUCGUAUUCGCCCUGUAUGCCCACAUACAGUACGAGGGCUUCACGCCCAGUGCAGAGCGGCGGUCUCGGCUGGACAGCAGCGAGCUUCUGAGGCAGGAGGCCAACACCCCCGUGACCCGCUUCAACACCACCAAGGUUGUCAGCACCUUCAACCUGCCGUUGCUGCUGUCCGUGAGCAGCAGCACGCAGGACGGUGAGAUCAUGCACACUCGCUACGAGCUGGUCACCACCGUGCACCUGCCCUGGUCCCUGACCAGCCUCAAGGCCAAAGUUCCCAUCAUCAUCACCAGCGCCUCAGUGGACUCUGCCAUCUGCCAGCUGUCAGAGGACGGAGUGUUACCCGUGAACCCAGAUCACCAGAAUUAAGUGCCCGAACUUUUAAAUAUUAAAAGCUUUAUUAGUCUCUACCAGGAGGAAGCCCUCUCUCUUGCACAGGUGACUCUCAGAGGAGUCGAGGAGUGGGCAACAGGUUGUCUGCAACCUCCCCAAGCUCUAGCGGUUUAGGUAUCUGUGUCUCCCCUCCCUAGAACUAUCACUGAAUGCCUGGAAUGGACAAAGGAAACCGGGAAGGUCUCCCAGGACCCAAACCCGGCAUAACCUGCCUUUUCCACCCUGAGUCUGCCCCAGCCUACUGGGGUCUCACAGUGCCAAGACCAGGGGUCCUACUUGGGGAGAAUUCUCCCCUCUGCUAAUGUCUGGUUGUAUUGGCUGUCACAACUGCAGGGGAUCGGGGGAGAAGAGUCUUAUUGGCGUGGAGAGGGUGGAGGCCAGGGACGCUGUUCAGCACCCUGCAGUGUCCAGGACGGCCCCCACAAUCAGGAAUUGUUUAUCCUGAAUGUCAACAGUACCAAGGGGGCUGAGCAUGGUGGCUCAUUCCUGUAAUCCCAGGACUUUAGGAGGCCAUGGCUGGAGGAUCACUUGAGACCAGGAGUUUGAGACAAGCCUGGGCAACACUGUGAGACCCCCAUCUCUACA